GGGCAUCUCCAGGACAGGCAUUCAGGCAGAGCAAGCUCCAGGUUUCACCACAAUGCCCAUCCCUGCCUCCCCACUCCACCCACCUCUGCCUUCCUUACUGCUGUAUCUGCUGCUUGAACUGGCAGGAGUCACACAUGUGUUCCAUGUGCAACAAACGGAGAUGUCACAGACUGUAUCAACUGGGGAGUCAAUCAUCUUGAGUUGCAGCGUACCCAAUACCUUACCAAAUGGACCUGUCUUGUGGUUCAAGGGAACAGGGCCAAACCGGAAAUUAAUCUACAAUUUCAAACAAGGUAACUUUCCCAGAGUAAAAGAGAUUGGAGACACCACCAAGCCUGGCAACACAGACUUUUCCACCCGCAUCCGUGAAAUCUCUCUUGCUGAUGCUGGCACCUAUUACUGCGUGAAGUUCAUAAAAGGAAGAGCUAUCAAGGAGUACCAAUCAGGUCGGGGCACUCAGGUGUUUGUUACUGGCUAUACCCCAUGGCAAAGAAGAGGAAUCAACUGCACCAAAAUAAUCCAUCCAGUCACUCAACAACUGUACAAGCAGAUGACAAUAACAAGCCUCGGUGGUUGUGAGGAAGACCAAUAUCCAGAGUUUCUACAAUGUAUUAUCUAAGAUGUCCAGUUUCAAAAAAAGUGAGACAUGCAAUAGAACAGAAAACUAUGACAAGUAUACCAAAAACAAACCAAAAAAAAAAAGGUAUCAGAAACUGCUUGUUAUGGCCAUCAGAUGUCAAACUUAACAGGCAAAGCAUUUGGUGUAACCAUUACAAAUAUGUUCAAAGAAACAUGAUUAAACAAACCAUGAUUAAAUAAGUACAAGAAAGUAACAUGAUAAUGUUGCAUCAAAUAGAAGAUAUCAAUAAACAGAAAUUAUUAAAAAGAACCAAAUGGAAAUUUUAUUAUUCAAAAGUACAACAAUUGAAAGAAAAAUUACCCUAGAGGGGAUUAACAGUAGAUUUGAAGAAGCAGAUUUAGCAAAUUUGAAAAUAGAUUAAUAUAAAUUAUGGAAUCUGAAGAACAGAGAAAAAUUAAAUGAAAAUAACAUUUAAAAAAUGAACAGAGCCUCAGAGAAAUGUAAGCCAUCAUUAAGCACACCGCAUACAUGUAAUAGGGAUAGCAGAAGGAGAGGAGAAAGAGAAAACAGCAGAAAAAAAUAUUCAAAGAAAGAAUAGCUGAAAACUUCUCAAGUCUAUUUAGUCAGCUGGACCGGAGACUGAAAAAGGAAACUCAAAUUACUAGAAUCAGAAAUGAAGGAAGGAACAUUACUAGCAACUUUAUAGAAAUAAAAAGGAAUAUUAAAGAAUACUAUGAAAAAAUGUGUGCCUAUAAACUAGGUUUAUAUGAUGAAAAAGACAAACUCCUAGAAGACAUAAAAAUUACCAAAACUGGCCCAAAAAUAAUGGAGCAUUUCAAGAUACCUAUAACAACUAAACAGAUUAAAUUAGUAAUAAAAAAUUACCCUGAUAUCGACACCAGACAAAGACAUCACAAGAAAAAAACACAGAUCAAAUAUAUCUUACGUAUAUGGACACAAAAAUCCCUUAAGAAAAUACUAGCAAACUGAAACCAGCAACAUAUAGAAAGCAUUAUUCAUGUUGACCAAGUGGGAUUUAUCCCAUGAAUACAAGGUUGGUUUAAUAUCUGAAUGUCAAUUAAUUUAAUACAACACAAUAUCAAUAAAAUAAAAAAGAAAACCACAUAAUCCUCUCAAGAUGAUAAAAAAAAAGGAAUUUGGUAAAAUCUAAAAUUCUUUUAUUUAAAAAGGUACUCAAAAAACUAGGAAUAGUAGGGAACUUUAUCAACCUGAUAAAGAGCAUGGAUGCAAAACCCAUAGCUAACAUCAUAUUUAGCAAAACCGAAAGCCACAGCCAAUGUCACAAUUAAUGAGGAUGGUUAGAUGCUGUCCCCAGUAGAUCAAGAAUAACACAAGGAUAUCUCCUAUCACCAUUUCUACUCAACGUUGUACUAAAAUUUUUAGUCAGGACAAUUAAGUAAUAAAAACAAUCCAAAUUGGAAAGAAUGAAGUAAAACUAUCUCUAUUGACAAAUGGCAUGUUCUUGUACAUAGAAAAUCCUAAGGAACCCACUAAAAAACUAUUCAAACUACUGAGCAAGUUCAGCAAGCUUGAGAGUACAGUUCAAUAUACAAAAAUCUAUUACAUUUCCACACACUUGGAAUGAACACUAAAAAUAAAAAUAAAUUUAACAAAAGAAGUGCAAAUUUAUACUCUGAAAACUACAAAAAAAUGUUAAAUGAAAGAAGAUCUAAACAAAUUGAAAAUUUUCCCAUUUUCAUGGACCAGAAGAUUUAACAUUCUUAAGAUGGCACUAUUCCCCCAAACUGGUCUACAGAUCCAACACAAUCCUUAUCAGAAUCCCAACCUACUUUUUUGUAGAAAUUGACAAGCUGAUCUUAACAUUCAUGUGGAAAUAUGAAGGAUCCAGAAUAGCCAAAACAAUCCUGAAAAAUAAAGUAGGAGAACACACGUUUUUCUUUCAAAACUUACUACAGGCUGGACGCAAUGGCUCACGCCUGUAAUCCCAGCACUUUGGGAGGCUGAGAUGGGAGGAUCGCUUGAGGACAGGAGUUUGAGGCCAGCCUGGUGAACACAGUGAAAUCUCAUCUCUAAAAAUAAAUAAAUAAAAUAAAAAUAAAAGUUCACUACAAGUCCACAUCAAUCAAGAUAAUGUGGUACUGGAACAGGAUAGACCUAUAGACCAAUGGAAAAGAGAGAGUCCAGAAACAAGCCCAUGUAUCUGUGGUCAACUGAUUUUCAACAAGUGUGAUAAUGAGGAAAGAAGCAUCUUUUCAACAAAUAAUGCUGAAACAACUGGAUAGCCACACACAGAAAACAAUGAAGUUGAACCCUACUUCACACCAUAUACAAAAAUUAACUCAAAAUGGUUUGAAAGCCUAAAAAUACCUAUAAAGCUUUUAUAAUAAAACAUAGGGAUAAAUCUUAAUGACAUCAGAUUUUGCAUUGGCUUCUUAAGCAUAGUAUCAAAAGCAUGAGAAACAAAAGAAAAAAUAGAUAUAUUGGACUUCAUAAAAAUUAAAACCUUUUAUGCUUCAAAGGACAUUAUCAAGAAAGUAAAAAGAUAACCCACAGAAUGGGAAAAAUAUUUGCAAAUUACAUAUCUGAUAAGGGCCUUGAGUUUAGAAUAUAUAAAGAAUUUCUCCAAAGCAGAUAUUCAAAUUGCCAAUAAGCACAUCAAAAGGAGCUCAGCAUAAUUUAUCCUCAGGGAAAUGCAAAUCAAAACUAUAAUGAAAUACAACUUUGCACUCAUAAGGAUAGCUAAAAUCAAAAAUCAGAUAACAAAUGUUUAUGAGAAUGUAGAGGAAUUGUAAACCUCAUACACUGCAGGUGGAAAUGCAAAAUGGUGAAGCCACUUUGGAAAAUAGAUAGGCAGCUCCUCAAACAGUCAAACAUAAGUUACUAUAUGACCCAGCUAUUCCACUCCUAGGUAUUUACUCAAGAGAAAUGAAAACAUAUGUUCACACAAAAAUUUGUGCACAAAUGUUUAUAACAGCAUUCACACUAUCUGAAAGGUAGAAACAAUCCAAACAUCUAUCAACUGAUGAAUGGAAAAGCAAGGUAUGAUCUAUACAUACAGUGGAAUAUUAUUAGGCUAUGAAGAGGAAUGACAUACUAAGACAUGCAGCAACAUGGAUAAACCUUGAAAGCAUAUGCUAAGUUAAAGAAUAAAAUCACAAAAGGUCACUUAUUCUCUCUAGAUUCUUCCUCUCUGUGCAGGACAUCUCUGAAAGAAAGACAGCAGCCCCAGUCAGGGGCUUAUAGAUAAAACUCCCAUCUCCCUGGGACAGAGCACCGGGGGGAAGGGGCAGCUGUGGGCACAGCUUCAGCAGACUUAAACAUUCCUGCCUGCCGGCUCUGAAGAGAGCAGUGGAUCUCCCAGCACAGCGCUUGAGCUCUGCUAAGGGACAGACUGCCUCCUCAAGUGGGUCGCUGACCCCCGUGCCUCCUGAUGGGGAGACACCUCCCAGCAGGGGUCGACAGACACCUCAUACAGGAGAGCUCUGGCUGGCAUCUGGCAGGUGCCCCUCUGGGAUGAAGCUUCCAGAGGAAGGAGCAGGCAGCAAUCUUUGCUGUUCUGCAGUCUCCACUGGUGAUACCCACGAAAACAGGAUCUGGAGUGGACCUCCAGCAAACUCCAGCAGACCUGCAGAAGAGUGGCCUGACUGUCAAAAGGAAAACUAACAAACAGAAAGCAACAGGAUCAACAUCAACAAAAAGGAUGAGCAUGCAAAAAUCCCAUCAGAAGGUCACCAACAUCCAAGAUCAAGGUAGAUAAAUCCAUGAAAAUGAGGAAAAAACAGCGCAAAAAAGCUGAAAACUCCAAAAACCAGAAUGUCUCUUCUCCUCCAAAGAAUGACAUCUCCUCGCCAGCAAGGCAACAAAACUGGAUGGAGAAUGAGUUUGACGAAUUGACAGAAGUAGGCUUCAGAUGGCGGGUAAUAACAAACUCCUCCAUGCUAAAAGAGCAUGUUCUAACCCAAUGCAAGAAAGCUAAGAAACUUGAUAAAAGGUUGCAGGAACUGCUAACUAGAAUAACCAGUUUAGAGAAGAACAUAAAUGACCUGAUGGAGCUGAAAAACACAACACGAGAACUUCAUGAAGCAUACAGAAGUAUCAAGAGCUGAAUCAAUCAACCAGAAGAAAGGAUUUCAGAGAUUGAAGAUCAACUUAAUGAAAUAAAGUAUGAAGACAAGAUUAGAGAAAAAAGAGUGAAAAAGAAUG